ACUGCCCUCGCUUCCUGCGCCUCUUCAGGUCACCGCUUGCUCUAGUUCCCAGGCUUUGGCCUCUAGUGGAUGAGAAUCACCGAGUCUGCGGGGCUGGACGCUGACCGCCCGGGCCAGCACCUAGGCGGGCGGGAGCUGUGCGGCCCAGGGUUCGCGCGGGCCGGGUAGAGGCUCGAGCCGGGACCCCCGAGCGUGAACCCCGGAGCCAGCGGCGCUGGGGCCAGAGGGGCCAGGCGGGAGGUGGUGGCGGAGGCGAAGGGGCGACGGGACCUGGGCCUGGCCCGUGUGUGUCCUCGGCGGCCUGGCGCCGGCCGUCGCUGUACGGUGAGCCCCAGGGAGGCGGAUCUGGGCCCCGAGAAGGACACCCGCCUGGAUUUGCCCCGUAGGCCCGGCCCGGGCCCCUCGGGAGCAGAACAGCCUUGGUGAGGUGGACGGGAGGGGACUUCGCGAGCAGACGCGCGCGCCAGCGACAGCAGCCCGCCCCGGCCUCUCGGGAGCCGUGGGGCAGAGGCUGCAGAGCCCCAGGAGGGGGCCAGUGUCAUUCAAAGAUGUGGCUGUGGAUUUCACCCAGGAGGAGUGGUGGCAACUGGACCCUGAUGAGAAGAUAACAUACGGGGAUGUGAUGUUGGAGAACUACAGCCAUCUAGUUUCCCUGGCUUAUGAGGUGGCAACAUCUUGUACUUCGGAGAUCUGAAGCCGAGCAACUUGCCCAAGUCCUUCUUCUUUUCCCAUUAACAAGAUAUGAUAUCACCAAGCCAAACGUCAUCAUUAAGUUGGAGCAGGGAGAGGAGCUGUGGAUAACGGGAGGUGAAUUUCCAUGUCAACAUAGUCCAGCCCUUCACAUCCUCAGCCGAAGAUCUCACUUCCUCCCAGAGGCCUUUGCUGACUGACCCCUCAGGGAUUGUGGGACUUUACCAAAUCGGUUUGUAAUAACACCUAGAAGACGCUAUCCGAUCCAUCAGGCCCAGUAUUCCUGUCUGGGGGUACUUCCCACCGUGUGCUGGAAUGGUUAUCACAAGAAGGCUGUGCUGUCCCCUCGCAACUCCAGGAUGGUGUGUAGCCCAGUGACUGUGAGGAUCGCCCCUCCUGACAGAAGAUUUUCGCGUUCUGCGAUACCAGAGCAGAUAAUCAGCUCAACACUGUCCUCACCAUCAAGUAACGCCCCAGACCCAUGUGCAAAGGAGACAGUACUGAGUGCCCUCAAAGAGAAGGAGAAGAAAAGGACAGUGGAGGAAGAAGACCAAAUAUUCCUUGAUGGCCAGGAAAAUAAAAGAAGGCGCCAUGAUAGCAGUGGCAGUGGACAUUCAGCAUUUGAGCCCCUGGUGGCCAAUGGAGUCCCCGCUUCUUUUGUGCCUAAGCCUGGGUCUCUGAAGAGAGGCCUCAAUUCUCAGAGCUCAGAUGACCACUUGAAUAAGAGAUCCCGAAGCUCUUCCAUGAGCUCCUUGACAGGCGCUUACGCAAGUGGCAUCCCUAGCUCCAGCCGCAAUGCCAUUACCAGUUCCUACAGCUCCACUCGAGGCAUCUCACAGCUCUGGAAGAGAAAUGGCCCCAGUUCAUCACCCUUCUCUAGCCCAGCCUCCUCCCGCUCCCAGACACCGGAGAGGCCAGCAAAGAAAAUAAGAGAAGAGGAGCUGUGUCAUCAUUCCAGUUCUUCAACUCCAUUGGCAGCAGACAGGGAGUCCCAGGGAGAAAAGGCUGCAGAUACAACCCCAAGGAAGAAACAAAACUCGAAUUCUCAGUCUACACCUGGCAGCUCUGGGCAGCGUAAGCGGAAAGUUCAGCUGCUGCCUUCUCGGCGAGGGGAACAGCUGACCUUGCCUCCACCUCCCCAGCUUGGCUAUUCGAUCACUGCCGAGGACCUAGACUUAGAGAAGAAGGCUUCAUUACAGUGGUUCAACCAGGCCUUGGAGGACAAGAGCGAUGCUGCCUCGAACUCUGUCACUGAGACCCCACCUAUCACUCAGCCUUCAUUUACCUUUACCCUGCCUGCUGCUGCACCUGCCUCCCCACCCACCUCCCUCCUGGCCCCAAGCACCAACCCACUGUUAGAGAGCUUGAAGAAGAUGCAGACUCCCCCGAGCCUGCCACCCUGCCCAGAAUCUGCUGGAGCAGCAACCACUGAGGCCCUCUCACCUCCAAAGACACCCAGCCUCCUACCCCCGCUGGGUUUAUCACAGUCAGGGCCGCCAGGGCUGCUCCCCAGCCCCUCCUUUGACUCCAAACCCCCGACCACUUUGCUGGGGCUGAUCCCUGCUCCAUCCAUGGUACCAGCCACUGACACCAAGGCACCUCCAACCCUUCAGGCAGAGACGGCUACCAAACCCCAAGCCACAUCUGCCCCGUCCCCCGCCCCCAAGCAAAGCUUCCUGUUUGGAACACAGAACACCUCACCUUCCAGCCCUGCCGCCCCUGCUGCAUCUUCAGCACCUCCCAUGUUCAAGCCCAUUUUCACGGCUCCACCCAAGAGUGAGAAGGAAGGCCCCACACCGCCUGGCCCUUCAGUCACAGCCACAGCGCCCUCCAGCUCCUCCCUCCCCACGACCACCAGCACCACAGCCCCGACCUUCCAGCCUGUCUUUAGCAGCAUGGGGCCACCUGCAUCUGUGCCCUUGCCUGCUCCCUUCUUCAAGCAGACAACUACUCCCGCCACUGCUCCCACCACAACUGCCCCGCUCUUCACUGGCCUGGCCAGCGCCACCUCUGCUGUGGCUCCCAUCACCUCUGCCAGUCCAUCCACAGACUCUGCUUCGAAGCCUGCGUUUGGCUUUGGCAUAAACAGUGUGAGCAGCAGCAGUGUGAGUACCACGACCAGCACCGCCACUGCCGCCUCACAGCCUUUCCUCUUCGGGGCGCCCCAGGCCUCUGCUGCCAGCUUCACCCCGGCCAUGGGCUCCAUAUUCCAGUUUGGCAAACCUCCUGCCUUGCCCACAACCACCACAGUCACCACCUUCAGCCAGUCCCUGCACACUGCCGUGCCAACGGCCACCAGCAGCAGCGCUGCCGACUUUAGUGGUUUUGGCAGCACCCUCGCCACCUCCGCCCCGGCCACCAGCAGCCAGCCCACUCUGACGUUCAGUAACACGAGCACCCCCACGUUCAACAUUCCCUUUGGCUCAAGCGCCAAGUCCCCGCUCCCAUCAUAUCCGGGAGCCAACCCCCAGCCCGCAUUUGGGGCCGCUGAGGGGCAGCCACCGGGGGCCGCCAAGCCGGCCCUUGCCCCCAGCUUUGGCAGCUCUUUCACUUUUGGAAACUCUGCAGCCCCGGCUGCUGCACCCACACCUGCACCUCCGUCCAUGAUCAAGGUCGUGCCUGCGUACGUGCCUACGCCCAUCCAUCCUAUCUUUGGCGGUGCCACGCACUCGGCGUUUGGGUUGAAAGCCACGGCUUCGGCCUUCGGCGCUCCCGCCAGCUCACAGCCCGCCUUUGGCGGCUCCACUGCUGUCUUCUUCGGUGCAGCCACCAGCUCCGGCUUUGGAGCCACCACCCAGACCGCCAGCAGCGGGAGCAGCAGCUCGGUGUUUGGCAGCACAACACCAUCACCCUUCACGUUUGGGGGUUCGGCAGCCCCCGCUGGCAGUGGGAGCUUUGGGAUCAAUGUGGCCACCCCAGGCUCCAGCACCACCACCGGAGCUUUCAGCUUUGGAGCAGGACAGAGUGGGAGCACAGCCACCUCCACCCCCUUCGCAGGGGGCUUAGGUCAGAACGCCCUGGGCACCACCGGCCAGAGCACACCGUUUGCCUUCAACGUGAGCAGCACAACUGAGAGCAAACCUGUGUUUGGAGGCACCGCCACCCCCACCUUUGGUCUGAACACCCCUGCGCCUGGAGUGGGCACAUCAGGCAGCAGCCUCUCCUUUGGGGCAUCCUCAGCACCCGCCCAAGGCUUUGUUGGUGUUGCACCUUUCGGCAACACUUUUGCUCACCAGCAAGAACACAGCCCGAGGAAGGGACCCAAUAACCUUUCAAAACGCAAACUGCUGCCUGCGGUGAGGGCCCAGGGUCUUCCACGGAGAGGACAGGCAUCUUCCUUUCCCACCAGGAAGGAGUGAGCCCGGAGCCUCUGCUAUGUGCAAGGCGGUGUGCAAGCACCGGCUGCAGCUUUUUGCUCUCUUCUUUCUCUUUGGGGCUGGGCUGGGUGUGCGUUCUGGUGCUGAUGCUUUGGCCUGUGAGGCUGAGCUAGAGAAAUGUAGAUGUUAGAUGUGCCAGUACCAUCCUGCGCCUCCCAAGCAUGCCCCCACUCACUCACGUCGGCAUCUCGACCCGUUCAAUUACAGCAACGAAGAAGCCACCGCUAAGCGUGGUCUUGGGGGAAGCCCGGAGGCAGUGCUCGGCACCCGGGAACGUGCUCAGGCCUCGGUGGGGCCGGGCAGGCAGGGCGGGAGCUAGCCUGCAAGAGAAACAGCCCCAAUGCUGGGUAAGAGAGCAGUUCACCCCAUCCCCCCCUCCACGACCCUGGCGCACGCCCUGUACCUGAAGGCGCCCGGGUUCUGCUGCAGCGCAUCUUGUACCAUGUCUUCAUUCUCCUCCUGGCAGAGGGAGCACAUGGAGUAGACGAGCCGCUGCAGGGAAGGGAAAGUGAGCGCGUGGCACAGGGCUCGCUGCUGGAACCCUGCCAGGGCAUGCAGACGCACCGGGCUAGGUGUCCCUGCCCCGGGCUCCUCCAGCUGUCUGCUCGGCAUACCUAAGGAAAAGCGUGUCUCGGUUACACAGCUUCACAGGCUGCCUCAGUCCUGAAAUCCUCGCUCCUGAAAUCCUCGCUUCACAGAGGAGAACUUUUGCUCCAGGGUCCCAAGCCCAUUAAAGUGUCAGAACUAAGACCAAAACAGAUGACUCCAGGUCUAAGCUGCUGUGGACCUCUGAGUCCCUCAGCCACGCCUUCUCACCAUCUCACCCGAGCCACUGCAGGAAGGAUCCAGCAGGACAUAGUGGACCUCACGAUAGCGCGGAUCUAAGGGGGAGACCGCCAGGAAGUCCUCCUCAGCCAGCUCACAGCAGGAGACGCCAGCCCAGGCCAGCAGCGUGGCCAUGGAUGCCAGCCGCCUGGCAUCCAGGUCAAAGGCAAAGAUCUUCCUAGGGCAGAGGGCAGAGCAGGGGUGAGCUGAGCAUGCAUGGAGCAGCUAAGGGCCUGUCACAGCUGACACAGACAACCAGAACAUGCAGGUUAAGCCAGGACACACAAUAUUGAAACAGCCUAUAUUUAAAGGGCCCAGGGUCAGAGGUAACUGGCCUGGGGUCUCUGCCCCAAGGGCUAAGGGAUCCACAUCUCACACCUGCAGUGGGGAAAGCUUAGCUUGGGGCAAAUACCGUGAACUACUUUGGUGCAGCAGGAAAGAGUUAAGCGAAAGUCAUCCUUUCAGCCUUCAUUACCCACUGAAAGGCACAAAAUCAAACCCCAUGUCCUCCUCCUCCUCCUGUGGCACUCACCCUUGGUUCUUCAGAAGAGCAGCCAAGUGACUGGUCUUUAUUGCCUGGGGUGGCACAGGCAUCCAUGACAUGGGAGCCUGGCGGGGGUCCAGCAGCAUGGCUGGGAGACAGCUGGCCUGGCAGGCAGAACACAGGGGCCGGGUAAACAGAGACCCCAGGCUAGGCCCUUCCCGUGCCUACACAUUCUUCCCUUUUCUAUUCCUCUUGCCUACCCUGUCCUGCAGAAUGAGGUGUCCGGCCCGGUACAGUGGGUGUUCAUGCAGAUCUGUCUGGGCGGGAAACACCAGCAGCUCCGGCAUCAAGGGGUCCAGGAGAAAAUGCUUCCCCUUGAGGGCUCGUAAGUCAUCGAGGCUGCCAGGGAAGAACCAUUCAUUCAUCAUUUCCUGAAUUUCUCCCUGCCAGGCCCUAUUUCAACGGUCCAUUCAUGCAACAAAUGUUACCACAGCUAUGGAGAAAUCAACAGGGUGAUAAGGGAAUCCGGGAUCCGCAGUUGAGGGAAUGGGUUGUCAAGCCAGACUUAUGGGUCAGGAGCCCCCUCUACUGUUUACCAGCAGUGGGAGCCUGGGCAAGUGAUUCAAUCUCAAGCCCCACUGGCAUCUCUGUAAAAUAGUAGGUGUGAGGAUUCAAUGAGCCAAUAUAUCCAAGAUACUUACGUGCCACAAUUUAAUAAAUGUUAGCUAUUCCUGUUGAAGCAUAACCUUGGAGAAAGGUUACUUUACAGGGGGGUGAGGAGUGGGGAAGUGAGAGCUGAGCUCAUUCUUGAUGGAUGAGGAGUUAGUCAUGUGAGGCGCUUAGGUUAAAACUACAUUCACUAUAACUCAGUAAAGCAGUCCCGCCCACUCUCCGACCCAUGCAGAAAUAGGCCUAGGGAGUCACAUGUCUCAGUUCAGAAAUCUAUCGAAGUGGCAGAGCUGGAAUUCAAACACAAGCAGCCGUUCUCUGCUAUUCCACCCUGGUGUCCAAGCAACAUGGUAGGGCAGAAGGAAGAGGAUCUUACAAAGAGUAAGGGAAAGGGAGAGGGGCAGAGGCUGCUUCUCAGAGCCACCAAAGGACAAAAUAAGACAGGUGUGAGCCCAGUGGAGGAGGCACGGGGCAGAGACCAGCCACUGUUGCUGGCACGCUGGUGCACGUAGCACUGUGGCAGAUGGACCUGGAGAGGAAGCAGGAGGGACAGCACAAUGGAGCCAAGAAAGGACUUAGCAUGGCCGGGCGCGGUGGUUCAUGCCUGUAAUCCCAGCAUUUUGGGAGGCCAAGGUGGGCAGAUCACCUGAGGUCAGGAGUUUGAGACCAGCCUGGCCAACAUGGAGAAAUCCCGUCUCUACUAAAAAUACAAAAUUAGCCAGGCAUGGUGCUGCAUGCCUGCAAUCCUGUAGGGAAAAGAAAGAGAGAUCAGACUGUUACUGUGUCUGUGUAGAAAGGGAAGACAUAAGAAAUUCCAUUUUGACCUGUACCUUGAACAAUUGGUUGGCUGAGAUGCUGUUAAUUUGUGACUUUGCCCCAAAUUUGAGCUCACAAAAACAUGUGUUGUAUGGAAUCAAGGUUUAAAGGAUCUAGGGCUGUGCAGGACAUGCCUUGUUAAUAAAACGUUUACAAGCAGUAUGCUUGGUAAAAGUC